ACUCCGGAACAGCGCGCUCGCAGCGGGAGGUCGCGAAGCCUGGGACUGUGUCUGUCGCCCAUGGCCGCCGCGCUGCUCGCCCGGGCCUCGGGCCCUGCCCGCAGAGCUCUCUGUCCUAGGGCCUGGCGGCAGUUACACACCAUCUACCAGUCUGUGGAACUGCCCGAGACACACCAGAUGUUGCUCCAGACAUGCCGGGACUUUGCCGAGAAGGAGUUGUUUCCCAUUGCAGCCCAGGUGGAUAAGGAACAUCUCUUCCCAGCGGCUCAGGUGAAGAAGAUGGGCGGGCUUGGGCUUCUGGCCAUGGACGUGCCCGAGGAGCUUGGCGGUGCUGGCCUCGAUUACCUGGCCUACGCCAUCGCCAUGGAGGAGAUCAGCCGUGGCUGCGCCUCCACCGGAGUCAUCAUGAGUGUCAACAACUCUCUCUACCUGGGGCCCAUCUUGAAGUUUGGCUCCAAGGAGCAGAAGCAGGCGUGGGUCACGCCUUUCACCAGUGGUGACAAAAUUGGCUGCUUUGCCCUCAGCGAACCAGGGAACGGCAGUGAUGCAGGAGCUGCGUCCACCACCGCCCGGGCCGAGGGCGACUCAUGGGUUCUGAAUGGAACCAAAGCCUGGAUCACCAAUGCCUGGGAGGCUUCGGCUGCCGUGGUCUUUGCCAGCACGGACAGAGCCCUGCAAAACAAGGGCAUCAGUGCCUUCCUGGUCCCCAUGCCAACGCCUGGGCUCACGUUGGGGAAGAAAGAAGACAAGCUGGGCAUCCGGGGCUCAUCCACGGCCAACCUCAUCUUUGAGGACUGUCGCAUCCCCAAGGACAGCAUCCUGGGGGAGCCAGGGAUGGGCUUCAAGAUAGCCAUGCAAACCCUGGACAUGGGCCGCAUCGGCAUCGCCUCCCAGGCCCUGGGCAUUGCCCAGACCGCCCUCGAUUGUGCUGUGAACUACGCUGAGAAUCGCAUGGCCUUCGGGGCGCCCCUCACCAAGCUCCAGGUCAUCCAGUUCAAGUUGGCAGACAUGGCCCUGGCCCUGGAGAGUGCCCGGCUGCUGACCUGGCGCGCUGCCAUGCUGAAGGAUAACAAGAAGCCUUUCAUCAAGGAGGCAGCCAUGGCCAAGCUGGCCGCCUCGGAGGCCGCGACCGCCAUCAGCCACCAGGCCAUCCAGAUCCUGGGCGGCAUGGGCUACGUGACAGAGAUGCCGGCAGAGCGGCACUACCGCGACGCCCGCAUCACUGAGAUCUACGAGGGCACCAGCGAAAUCCAGCGGCUGGUGAUCGCCGGGCAUCUGCUCAGGAGCUACCGGAGCUGAGCCCGCGGCGGACUGCCCCAGGACUGCGGGAAGGCGCGGGAGCCAGGGGCCUCCACCCCAACCCCGGCUCAGAGACUGGGCGGCCCGGCGGGGGCUCCCUGGGGACCCCAGAUGGGCUCAGUGCUGCCACCCAGAUCAGAUCACAUGGGAAUGAGGCCCUCCGACCAUUGGCAGCUCCGCCUCUGGGCCUUUCCGCCUCCUCACCACUGUGCCUCAAGUUCCUCAUCUAAGUGGCCCUGGCCUCCUGGGGGCGGGGUUGUGGGGGGGCUGAGCGACACUCAGGGACACCUCAGUUGUCCUCCCGCGGGCCCUGGUGCCCUGGCAUGAAGGCCCAGUGCGACAGGCCCUUGGUGGGGUCUGUCUUUUCCUUGAGGUCAGAGGUCAGGAGCAGGGCUGGGGUCAGGAUGACGAGGCCUGGGGUCCUGGUGUUGGGCAGGUGGUGGGGCUGGGCCAUGGAGCUGGCCCAGAGGCCCCUCAGCCCUUUGUAAAGUCUGAUGAAGGCAGGGGUGGUGAUUCAUGCUGUGUGACUGACUGUGGGUAAUAAACACACCUGUCCCCCA